GUCGGUUGGGACGCGGAGCUGAGGAGCAGGGCCGGGCGCCAUGGCACCGUGGGGCAAGCGGCUGGCUGGCGUGCGCGGGGUGCUGCUUGACAUCUCGGGCGUGCUGUACGACAGCGGCGCGGGCGGCGGCACGGCCAUCGCCGGCUCGGUGGAGGCGGUGGCCAGACUGAAGCGUUCCCGGCUGAAGGUGAGGUUCUGCACCAACGAGUCGCAGAAGUCCCGGGCAGAGCUGGUGGGGCAGCUUCAGAGGCUGGGAUUUGACAUCUCUGAGCAGGAGGUGACCGCCCCGGCACCAGCUGCCUGCCAGAUCCUGAAGGAGCAAGGCCUGCGACCAUACCUGCUCAUCCAUGACGGAGUCCGCUCAGAAUUUGAUCAGAUCGACACAUCCAACCCAAACUGUGUGGUAAUUGCAGACGCAGGAGAAAGCUUUUCUUAUCAAAACAUGAAUAACGCCUUCCAGGUGCUCAUGGAGCUGGAAAAACCUGUGCUCAUAUCACUGGGAAAAGGGCGUUACUACAAGGAGACCUCUGGCCUGAUGCUGGACGUUGGUCCCUACAUGAAGGCGCUUGAGUAUGCCUGUGGCAUCAAAGCCGAGGUGGUGGGGAAGCCUUCUCCUGAGUUUUUCAAGUCUGCCCUGCAAGCGAUAGGAGUGGAAGCCCACCAGGGGACAGCUGUCUUUGUGCUUAUUGAAGCACUUUAACGAAGCAGUUUUCACAGCUGCAUACUAUUCCACUGUUCAGACUCCCGUCAUAUUCUUGACCAUUUCCUAUUGAUGGAGAUGAGGCUGCUUCCAGUUUCGCUCUUGUGCGUAACCCUGAUGAACACAUCUUGUAUGUACAUCCUCUUGUACAUUUCUAAUUAUUUGCUCCAAAUCCUAGUGGUGUGGCUGGGAGGCUGUGAUGCAUGUUGCUUAUUUCUGUUUCAGAAAGGUGUGUCCGUUCACCUUCCUGACCUGCUGCGUAUACAGAUGCUUGUUUCCCCACAUCCUUACCAACACCAUGAUUUCUGACUUUUUUUUUUUAAAGUGGUCUUUGAGUUUUGCUGUUAGUCUUGUUCCUUAUGAAGGUGUCCGACCACAGUGGCAAUUACUCAGCAUUGCACUGUCUCCAGGUCUCUGUGGGAGCCUGGGUUCCUUUGGGGCCUGGAUUCAGGGCUCAUCCUAGAGUGAGCUGUCAUCUCAGGGCAUCUCCCUGGGGGAUAUGUGCACCCCAGAGCUGCAGUUACAGACACUGAGCUCACUCCACCUUCACCACCCAGCCCUGCUGCUUCCCGCCCUAAUCCUCCUGGCAGAGCCCCUGGAUAAGGAAAAUAUUUGUGAACCACGGAAGCUCUUUGGUGCUGGAAUUUUGCACUCCAAAGCAUCGCCGCCUGUUAGAUGAUGUUUCCCUCCAGCACCUAGGACACUGAAGAGGAGACCAGGGCAGGCAGGCAGAUGCGUAAGAGGGAGGAUUGACUGCUGUAGCACCCGACCCAGGACACCUGCCUCUGGGACUGUGGCGCCUCCAUCCGGCUCUCUGGAUCCUGGGUUCUGGGGGGUCCGACCUUUCAUUUUUUUCUCCGCCUCACACCCCACCAUGUCGUGUCUGAAAGGAAGCGAAGCCCAGCCCUGGCAGGUGGAGUAUUUUUAUUUCCCCUGACAGCGCACCUCCUGACCUCUAUCUUCUUGCCAGUGAUUUUUUAAAUCCUAAAUGAUUUGGCAAUAAUUGCUCCUCCUUGCGUGAUUAUUGCCCUUCACCGAUAGUAAAUCUGGGAAUCCCCUGGGGUCCUGAGCGCACUUUGGUAUGCGGAGCCCACAAGCUGGCCUGGACAGGCAUCACUGCUCCAGGCAGCUGUGCACCCAGCCGGCCCUGGCGUCCCGGCCCCCAGCCUCCGCCUCCCUCGCCGACAGCUUCCCGGGGCUCUGCCUGGAGGCAGCCUCGCUUUAUCCCGCAGAACCUCCACGCUGUUCCUGCAUGAGAACUCUUCCUCCAAGAGACCACGUUCCUCUGGUCCUGUCUCCGUGGGCCACAUCCACAAAUGUUCCAGCCCAGGAAGAACCAAGUCUGUAUUCUGGGAGGGAAACCUGUGUGCUGUCUGGUUUUGUAUGUGGGAGGAGCAUGCACACAGUUUCAUUUUCCCCGGAAGCAUGGAGGUGUAGGAUGACAUGUAAUAUUUGGAAGACCCAUUGCAUUUCCAAGGAACCUUCUAGCAGGAUGGCCCUGGAGUCUCUGGCAGCAGUGGACAUGGUCCUGAAUUGGAGUGCUGUGAAUGUUCACUGCUGACCUCACGGUUUGAAGACAAUUCCUUGAGAAGGGCAGAGGGGACCCGAAUACGGGGGCUCUGGCCGGCCCUGCUGCCAGAUGCCAGCAGCCGUGGGGGCUUGCCCGGCCAGCCCUGGCUUUUCCCAACCCUCAGAGUGCCCCUUGUGCAUGCAGCAGACACUGGUGCUGGUCCCAUUCCCGGGAGCACGCGGUGCCACUGGCUGUGUCUUGCCUGGCCAGGUGUUGGUUUGAUAGACUCGAAAACCUCAUUUGGAUUUGGCAGGAUUUUCCCUAACAUCAGUCAUUCUGGAAAAAACACUUUGAAUUUUUACCAUAUCUGGGUAUUUUUACCAUAUCUGGGUACUUGCCACUAGCUCUAUUUACUUCACGUUUCUUAAAAUUGAUUCAUUUUAUUACUUAAAUAAAUGUAUUUUAAAAGGAACUUUUGAUGACUACUAUAAAUGGAAAACCAGAAUCUCUCACUUACCAUAAUAGAUUAAUCUAAAAAUAAAGACCACAUGAUUACAUUAAAA